GCACACGUACGUUCCUCAUGAAAGGGACGACGGGAGCUGCAUGAAAGCCGAAGUUAUGGACCGCUAGCAUCUGUCACUGGCCACCGGUUUCCGGGAGUAAGCGGCAGCUACCUUACAGCCCUGACACGAGCCGGGUGCUCUCUCUUCUCACCGCGGCCCACGUCUCCUCGCUGGCUCCGGUGGCCUCGCUGGGUCGCGAGGAGGCGGAGGACUGUACUCUGAGGCCAAAAGCCAGAGUCGGCCCUGAACGCCCACGACUCUCAGGGUCCAGAGGCCGUGAGACCGGCCGCGGCUGAAAGGUACCAGGGCCCCUGAUGCCGGAGCCCGUGUGCUCGGCCCUCUUGCAGACGGUACUUGCGGGCUGGGGUUUCUUUCCCCUGGGUUUCGGGCAGAGAACCCGUGCGGGGCGCGCCCGAAGCGCCCUUUGGUGUCCCUUGCUCUCCCCAUGGUCUCGGCCCCCCUCCUUCUAAGCGCGUGUACCCGCGACCUGCGUCUGCAAGUGCUGCUCCACACACAGCGGCCCCAUCUCGGCCCGGUCUUCCCUGCCUCCCGCUUGGCCCCUGUGCUGUAAGCUCGCCUGGACCCCAGGCCGGGCGGUGCAUAGCUCUGUGGCCUGUGGCCCCGUGCUCAGCAUGACCUAACCAGAAUUAAGCAGUGGACAAUGGGAUUUAGGCCCCCCAAACCCUCGUCCGAUGACAAUGGGAGGGGAAGUGUGAUUUUUCUCCCCUCGGAUGGAGCGUGCUCAGCUGUAGGAAUGUGACUCAACUUGCUGAAAUGAUUUUCUGCUCUGCGGACUGGUGCACCCUGUGACCCAGACAGAUGUGGAGGGUCCCACCGCUCUGAUUAGCAGAACCAAACCGUGAGUGAGGUAAAGAAACCAAGUGGAAGAGUGUUUCCUCCUCUGGCCGUAAAGCAGCUCAGAUUGGGACAGGGGCGUCUGCUGACAGUGGAGAGCAGUGGUGGGGGAAGGGGCUUGAGGAAGGUGGCACCCAGAGGGGUGGAGAGGAGAUGUCUGACUGAGGGCCAUCUGAGGUCACGGUGCAUCCUGAGGACAGAGCUGAGAUUGGAUAUCAACGAUGUGGGCUCAGCAGCCCUGGAGUAGGAGCUGGGAAGCUGUCCCCGCCCUACUCCGGACCGCCCCAAAGACUCCAUGGGAUGGACCUGAGUCAGCCGAAUCCUAGCCCCUUCCCUUGGGCCUGCUGUGGUGCUCGACAUCAGUGACAGACGGAAGCAGCAGACCAUCAAGGCUACGGGAGGCCCGGGGCGCUUGCGAAGAUGAAGUUUGGCUGCCUCUCCUUCCGGCAGCCUUAUGCUGGCUUUGUCUUAAAUGGAAUCAAGACUGUGGAGACGCGCUGGCGUCCUCUGCUGAGCAGCCAGCGGAACUGUACCAUCGCCGUCCACAUUGCUCACAGGGACUGGGAAGGCGAUGCCUGUCGGGAGCUGCUGGUGGAGAGACUCGGGAUGACUCCUGCUCAGAUUCAGGCCUUGCUCAGGAAAGGGGAAAAGUUUGGUCGAGGAGUGAUAGCGGGACUCGUUGACAUUGGGGAAACUUUGCAAUGCCCCGAAGACUUAACUCCCGAUGAGGUUGUGGAACUAGAAAAUCAAGCUGCACUGACCAACCUGAAGCAGAAGUACCUGACUGUGAUUUCAAACCCCAGGUGGUUACUGGAGCCCAUACCUAGGAAAGGAGGCAAGGAUGUAUUCCAGGUAGACAUCCCAGAGCACCUGAUCCCUUUGGGGCAUGAAGUGUGACAAGUGUGGGCUCCUGAAAGGAAUGUUCCAGAGAAACCAGCUAAAUCAUGGCACCUUCAAUUUGCCAUCGUGACGCAGACCUGUAUAAAUUAGGUUAAAGAUGAAUUUCCACUGCUUUGGAGAGUCCCACCCACUAAGCACUGUGCAUGUAAACAGGUUCCUUUGCUCAGAUGAAGGAAGUAGGGGGUGGGGCUUUCCUUGUGUGAUGCCUCCUUAGGCACACAGGCAAUGUCUCAAGUACUUUGACCUUAGGGUAGAAGGCAAAGCUGCCAGUAAAUGUCUCAGCAUUGCUGCUAAUUUUGGUCCUGCUAGUUUCUGGAUUGUACAAAUAAAUGUGUUGUAGAUGA